AGUCUCAGCGAAGCGUCUGCGACCGUCGUUUGAGUCGUCGCUGCCGCUGCCGCUGCCACUGCCACUGCCACCUCGCGGAUCAGGAGCCAGCGUUGUUCGCCCGACGCCUCGCUGCCGGUGGGAGGAAGCGAGAGGGAAGCCGCUUGCGGGUUUGUCGCCGCUGCUCGCCCACCGCCUGGAAGAGCCGAGCCCCGGCCCAGUCGGUCGCUUGCCACCGCUCGUAGCCGUUACCCGCGGGCCGCCACAGCCGCCGGCCGGGAGAGGCGCGCGCCAUGGCUUCUGGAGCCGAGUGAGUGUGCGCGCGCCGUUCGCUUGCUGCGGCGGCGCGCACCGGGACCAGCCGCGCAGGGUAGGCCCGGCGGGGCCUGGCCGUGGGCGCGUCAGAGAGGUGGAGACCAGGAAAGAGGGAAGGGAAGCUAGGGGGCGAGUGAGGGGCCGUGGACCCGGCAGGCCCGGCUGGGGCCAGCUGCGCACCCGCGCGCCCCCUAGGCGGGGCUUGCGUUGGGUCCGGGUCGGAGCCUGGGCCGGAUCGUGCUGUGUCAUGCAGGCCCCGGCCCGCCCGAUUGGCUCCCUUAGAACGGACGUCUGGGCCUGGCCAGGUCUUCCGGCCCACUCCGCCGGCGCGGCGCCCCGGGGCUUUGGGGCGCCAGUCUGCCGUCCGGCCUACCACCCGCCGAAAGCCUUUGGUCCCCGGAGAGAGCAGGCCCCGCGAGCCCGAGGCCCCAGCCGGGCCCGGUGGGCGUGGACUUUGCGCCAUGUGAAGGCCUCAGGAGCUCUGCCACCGAGGCGGAGCCCGGGGUCGGGGAAGGCCCGCCGAGCUCAGGGAAGCUCACAGCCGCCUUUUUGGAGCCGGGUCGGCGGGGCCGGAGUUCAAAAGGUGAUGACCUAUCAACAGCCAUUCUCAAACAGAAGAACCGUCCCAAUCGGUUAAUUGUUGAUGAAGCCAUCAAUGAGGACAACAGUGUGGUGUCCUUGUCCCAGCCCAAGAUGGAUGAAUUGCAGUUGUUCCGAGGUGACACAGUGUUGCUGAAAGGAAAGAAGAGACGAGAAGCUGUUUGCAUCGUCCUUUCUGAUGAUACUUGUUCUGAUGAGAAGAUUCGGAUGAAUAGAGUUGUUCGGAAUAACCUUCGUGUACGCCUAGGGGAUGUCAUCAGCAUCCAGCCAUGCCCUGAUGUGAAGUACGGCAAACGUAUCCAUGUGCUGCCCAUUGAUGACACAGUGGAAGGCAUUACUGGUAAUCUCUUCGAGGUAUACCUUAAGCCGUACUUCCUGGAAGCGUAUCGACCCAUCCGGAAAGGAGACAUUUUUCUUGUCCGUGGUGGGAUGCGUGCUGUGGAGUUCAAAGUGGUGGAAACAGAUCCUAGCCCUUAUUGCAUUGUUGCUCCAGACACAGUGAUCCACUGCGAAGGGGAGCCUAUCAAACGAGAGGAUGAGGAAGAGUCCUUGAAUGAAGUAGGGUAUGAUGACAUUGGUGGCUGCAGGAAGCAGCUAGCUCAGAUAAAGGAGAUGGUGGAACUGCCCCUGAGACAUCCUGCCCUCUUUAAGGCAAUUGGUGUGAAGCCUCCUAGAGGAAUCCUGCUUUACGGACCUCCUGGAACAGGAAAGACCCUGAUUGCUCGAGCUGUAGCAAAUGAGACUGGAGCCUUCUUCUUCUUGAUCAAUGGUCCUGAGAUCAUGAGCAAAUUGGCUGGUGAGUCUGAGAGCAACCUUCGUAAAGCCUUUGAGGAGGCUGAGAAGAAUGCUCCUGCCAUCAUCUUCAUUGAUGAGCUAGAUGCCAUCGCUCCCAAAAGAGAGAAAACUCAUGGCGAGGUGGAGCGGCGCAUUGUAUCACAGUUGUUGACCCUCAUGGAUGGCCUAAAGCAGAGGGCACAUGUGAUUGUUAUGGCAGCAACCAACAGACCCAACAGCAUUGACCCAGCUCUACGGCGAUUUGGUCGCUUUGACAGGGAGGUAGAUAUUGGAAUUCCUGAUGCUACAGGACGCUUAGAGAUUCUUCAGAUCCAUACCAAGAACAUGAAGCUGGCAGAUGAUGUGGACCUGGAACAGGUAGCCAAUGAGACUCACGGGCAUGUGGGUGCUGACUUAGCAGCCCUGUGCUCAGAGGCUGCUCUGCAAGCCAUCCGCAAGAAGAUGGAUCUCAUUGACCUAGAGGAUGAGACCAUUGAUGCCGAGGUCAUGAACUCUCUAGCAGUUACUAUGGAUGACUUCCGGUGGGCCUUGAGCCAGAGUAACCCAUCAGCACUGCGGGAAACCGUGGUAGAGGUGCCACAGGUAACCUGGGAAGACAUCGGGGGCCUAGAGGAUGUCAAACGUGAGCUACAGGAGCUGGUCCAGUAUCCUGUGGAGCACCCAGACAAAUUCCUGAAGUUUGGCAUGACACCUUCCAAGGGAGUUCUGUUCUAUGGACCUCCUGGCUGUGGGAAAACUUUGUUGGCCAAAGCCAUUGCUAAUGAAUGCCAGGCCAACUUCAUCUCCAUCAAGGGUCCUGAGCUGCUCACCAUGUGGUUUGGGGAGUCUGAGGCCAAUGUCAGAGAAAUCUUUGACAAGGCCCGCCAAGCUGCCCCCUGUGUGCUAUUCUUUGAUGAGCUGGAUUCGAUUGCCAAGGCUCGUGGAGGUAACAUUGGAGAUGGUGGUGGGGCUGCUGACCGAGUCAUCAACCAGAUCCUGACAGAAAUGGAUGGCAUGUCCACAAAAAAAAAUGUGUUCAUCAUUGGCGCUACCAACCGGCCUGACAUCAUUGAUCCUGCCAUCCUCAGACCUGGCCGUCUUGAUCAGCUCAUCUACAUCCCACUUCCUGAUGAGAAGUCCCGUGUUGCCAUCCUCAAGGCUAACCUGCGCAAGUCCCCAGUUGCCAAGGAUGUGGACUUGGAGUUCCUGGCUAAAAUGACUAAUGGCUUCUCUGGAGCUGACCUGACAGAGAUUUGCCAGCGUGCUUGCAAGCUGGCCAUCCGUGAAUCCAUCGAGAGUGAGAUUAGGCGAGAACGAGAGAGGCAGACAAACCCAUCAGCCAUGGAGGUAGAAGAGGAUGAUCCAGUGCCUGAGAUCCGUCGAGAUCACUUUGAAGAAGCCAUGCGCUUUGCGCGCCGUUCUGUCAGUGACAAUGACAUUCGGAAGUAUGAGAUGUUUGCCCAGACCCUUCAGCAGAGUCGGGGCUUUGGCAGCUUCAGAUUCCCUUCAGGGAACCAGGGUGGAGCUGGCCCCAGUCAGGGCAGUGGAGGCGGCACAGGUGGCAGUGUAUACACAGAAGACAAUGAUGAUGACCUGUAUGGCUAAGUGGUGGUGGCCAGCGUGCAGUGAGCUGGCCUGCCUGGACCUUGUUCCCUGGGGGUGGGGGCGCUUGCCCAGGAGAGGGACCAGGGGUGCGCCCACAGCCUGCUCCAUUCUCCAGUCUGAACAGUUCAGCUACAGUCUGACUCUGGACAGGGGGUUUCUGUUGCAAAAAUACAAAACAAAAGCGAUAAAAUAAAAGCGAUUUUCAUUUGGUAGGCGGAGAGUGAAUUACCAACAGGGAAUUGGGCCUUGGGCCUAUGCCAUUUCUGUUGUAGUUUGGGGCAGUGCAGGGGACCUGUGUGGGGUGUGAACCAAGGCACUACUGCCACCUGCCACAGUAAAGCAUCUGCACUUGACUCAAUGCUGCCCGAGCCCUCCCUUCCCCCUAUCCAACCUGGGUAGGUGGGUAGGGGCCACAGUUGCUGGAUGUUUAUAUAGAGAGUAGGUUGAUUUAUUUUACAUGCUUUUGAGUUAAUGUUGGAAAACUAAUCACAAGCAGUUUCUAAACCAAAAAAUGACAUGUUGUAAAAGGACAAUAAACGUUGGGUCAAAAUGGAGCCUGAGUCCUGGGCCCUGUGCCUGCUUCUUUUCCUGGGAACAGCCUUGGGCUACCCACCACUCCCAAGGCAUUCUUCCAAAUGUGAAAUCCUGGAAGUAAGAUUGCACCUUCUUCCUCUCCUGAUCAACAUCGGUAUGAUGUCUCCUGUUGCCUCACCCUUUGUCUGCAGUAUCACUGGAUAGGACUGGUGGAAAGGGAGCAGCCUGACAGAGCUCCAAAUGUGGAGAAUAUGGCAUCCCUCCACCUAUAUUUGAUGUGGACGGUAAGGCUAGGCCUGCAGGAUCCCUUAUCCUGACCAAAGACUGUGUUGGGGUGCCAUUUGAAAAUCGCAGGGUUGCAAAAGAAUACAAUCUUACUUGCAGGUGGAUAUUCUCUAUACUCUCUUUUAAUGCAUCUAAAAAUCCCAAACAUCCCCUGGUUGGUGAUCACUUACAGUUGUGUCCACCUUUAUUUUAUGUACUUUGAUUAAAAAAAAAAAACUUUUUGUUAAUAUAAAA